GCCACAGAGCAUCUUCAAGGAGCUGAACAAUGAGAACAAGAGCGCACUGCAGUUGGAGCAGCAAGUAAAGGAGCUACAGGAGAAGCUUGGUGAGGAGCACCUGGAAGCGGCCAGCCAGCAGAACCAGCAGCUAACGGCCCAGCUGAGCCUCAUGGCUCUCCCUGGGGAAGGACACGGAGGAGAACAUCUGGACAGUGAGGGGGAGGAGGCACCUCGGCCCAUGCCGAGUGUCCCAGAGGACCUGGAGAGCAGGGAGGCCAUGAGCAGCUUUAUGGACCACCUGGAGGAGAAGGCAGACCUGAGUGAGCUGGUGAAGAAAAAAGAACUUUGCUUCAUCCACCACUGGCGAGAUAGAUGCCAUCAGAAAAUCCAUCACCUUUUAUCAGAACCAGGGGGCCGUGCCAAAGAUGCGGCACUGGUAGGAGGACACCAUCAGGCUGGAGCUCAGGGAGGAGAUGAAGGUGAAGCUGCUGGAGCUGCAGCAGAUGGUGUUGCGGCUUAUAGCAACUACAACAAUGGGCACAGAAAAUUCCUGGCCACUGCCCAGAACCCUGCUGAUGAGCCCGGUCCAGGAGCCCCAGCCCCCCAGGAGCUUGGGGCUGCAGGCAAGCAUGGUGGUUAUCUAUUUCAGAUACCUGUUUGCUCAUAUUUACAUUCCUAACUGAACAAUGUCUGAAGAGGUACUUAAACCUGUCAUAAAACACAAAUGAGCUUAUGACCAAAUGCUUAGUGCCAGAAAAAACUUCAAACUGCAAUAUGAGUCUCUCCAAAUACAGAAAGGACCAGUAUUUUAAGAGGUGUGUUAACUAAAAUGUU